AGAGUGGACUGAGCAGCCAGUAGGGGAGAGAGCAGUUAAGGCACACAGAGCACCAGCUCCCUCCUGCCUGAAGAUGUUCCACCAAAUUUGGGCAGCUCUGCUCUACUUCUAUGGUAUUAUCCUUAACUCCAUCUACCAGUGCCCUGAGCACAGUCAACUGACAACUCUGGGCGUGGAUGGGAAGGAGUUCCCAGAGGUCCACUUGGGCCAGUGGUACUUUAUCGCAGGGGCAGCUCCCACCAAGGAGGAGUUGGCAACUUUUGACCCUGUGGACAACAUUGUCUUCAAUAUGGCUGCUGGCUCUGCCCCGAUGCAGCUCCACCUUCGUGCUACCAUCCGCAUGUGAGUGGAAAGAUGGGCUCUGUGUGCCCCGGAAAUGGAUCUACCACCUGACUGAAGGGAGCACAGAUCUCAGAACUGAAGGCCGCCCUGACAUGAAGACUGAGCUCUUUUCCAGCUCAUGCCCAGGUGGAAUCAUGCUGAAUGAGACAGGCCAGGGUUACCAGCGCUUUCUCCUCUACAAUCGCUCACCACAUCCUCCCGAAAAGUGUGUGGAGGAAUUCAAGUCCCUGACUUCCUGCCUGGACUCCAAAGCCUUCUUAUUGACUCCUAGGAAUCAAGAGGCCUGUGAGCUGUCCAAUAACUGACCUGUAACUUCAUCUAAGUCCCCAGAUGGGUACAAUGGGAGCUGAGUUGUUGGAGGGAGAAGCUGGAGACUUCCAGCUCCAGCUCCCACUCAAGAUAAUAAAGAUAAUUUUUCAAUCCUCA